AUUGUGGGAUUGGAUGAGUCUCAAGAUGGACAACCGGGAUGUUGCAGGAAAGGCUAACCGGUGGUUUGGGGUUGCUCCCCCUAAAUCUGGAAAAAUGAACAUGAACAUCCUUCACCAGGAAGAGCUCAUCGCUCAGAAGAAACGGGAAAUUGAAGCCAAAAUGGAACAGAAAGCCAAGCAGAAUCAGGUGGCCAGCCCUCAGCCCCCACAUCCUGGCGAAAUCACAAAUGCACACAACUCUUCCUGCAUUUCCAACAAGUUUGCCAACGAUGGUAGCUUCUUGCAGCAGUUUCUGAAGUUGCAGAAGGCACAGACCAGCACAGACGCCCCGACCAGUGCGCCCAGCGCCCCUCCCAGCACACCCACCCCCAGCGCUGGGAAGAGGUCCCUGCUCAUCAGCAGGCGGACAGGCCUGGGGCUGGCCAGCCUGCCGGGCCCUGUGAAGAGCUACUCCCACGCCAAGCAGCUGCCCGUGGCGCACCGCCCGAGUGUCUUCCAGUCCCCUGACGAGGACGAGGAGGAGGACUAUGAGCAGUGGCUGGAGAUCAAAGUUUCACCCCCAGAGGGAGCCGAGACUCGGAAAGUGAUAGAGAAAUUGGCCCGCUUUGUGGCAGAAGGAGGCCCCGAGUUAGAAAAAGUAGCUAUGGAGGACUACAAGGAUAACCCAGCAUUUGCAUUUUUGCACGAUAAGAAUAGCAGGGAAUUCCUCUACUACAGGAAGAAGGUGGCUGAGAUAAGAAAGGAAGCACAGAAGUCGCAGGCAGCCUCUCAGAAAGUUUCACCCCCAGAGGACGAAGAGGUCAAGAACCUUGCAGAAAAGUUGGCCAGGUUCAUAGCGGACGGGGGUCCCGAGGUGGAAACCAUUGCCCUCCAGAACAACCGUGAGAACCAGGCAUUCAGCUUUCUGUAUGAGCCCAAUAGCCAAGGGUACAAGUACUACCGACAGAAGCUGGAGGAGUUCCGGAAAGCCAAGGCCAGCUCCACAGGCAGCUUCACAGCACCUGAUCCCGGCCUGAAGCGCAAGUCCCCUCCUGAGGCCCUGUCAGGGUCCUUACCCCCAGCCACCACCUGCCCCGCCUCGUCCACGCCUGCGCCCACUAUCAUCCCUGCUCCAGCUGCCCCCGGGAAGCCAGCCUCCGCAGCCACCGUGAAGAGGAAGCGGAAGAGCCGGUGGGGGCCUGAAGAGGAUAAGGUAGAGCUCCCACCUGCUGAACUGGUGCAGAGGGACGUGGAUGCCUCUCCCUCGCCUCUGUCAGUUCAGGACCUCAAGGGGCUCGGCUAUGAGAAGGGGAAGCCUGUGGGUCUAGUGGGCGUCACAGAGCUUUCAGACGCCCAGAAGAAGCAGCUGAAGGAGCAGCAGGAGAUGCAGCAGAUGUACGACAUGAUCAUGCAGCACAAGCGGGCCAUGCAGGACAUGCAGCUGCUGUGGGAGAAGGCAGUCCAACAGCACCAGCACGGCUAUGACAGUGAUGAGGAGGUGGACAGCGAGCUGGGCACCUGGGAGCACCAGCUGCGGCGCAUGGAGAUGGAUAAGACCAGGGAAUGGGCCGAGCAGCUGACAAAGAUGGGCCGGGGCAAGCACUUCAUCGGAGACUUCCUGCCUCCAGACGAGCUGGAAAAGUUUAUGGAGACCUUCAAGGCCCUGAAGGAGGGCCGUGAGCCUGACUACUCAGAGUACAAGGAGUUCAAGCUGACUGUGGAGAACAUCGGCUACCAGAUGCUGAUGAAGAUGGGCUGGAAGGAGGGCGAGGGGCUGGGCUCAGAGGGCCAGGGCAUCAAGAACCCAGUGAACAAGGGCACCACCACAGUGGACGGCGCUGGCUUCGGCAUUGACCGGCCGGCGGAGCUCUCCAAGGAGGACGACGAGUAUGAGGCGUUCCGCAAGAGGAUGAUGCUGGCCUACCGCUUCCGGCCCAACCCCCUGAACAAUCCCAGACGGCCUUACUACUGAGUGUUCUGGAAAUACAUACUUUCUGAAUGACCAACCGUCCCUGGACUGUGGAAUGUUCCGGCCUGCAUUUCUGCCCACCCCUUCCGUUGUCACGAGUGCCGUGCCGUGUAAUAAAGUCCCAGUGCUCAUCCACCACAGAUGCCUGGUCCUGUUGCAGGAAGCCCCUCCUGUUAGCAGCGGGAUGCAAGAUGCUGUCUCGGGGCUCUCCUUAUUGGCCUGUGGAGUCUCCAUCCCCGCUCAGCCUGGGUUGCACUGGAGGGGAGGAAGAAAGUUGUUUUCAGCAUAGUAAAGCUGGAAGGCCAGGUGCAGUGUCUCACCCCUGUCAUCCCAGCACUUUGAGAGGCCAAGGCGGGCGGAUCACUGGAGGUCAGGAGUUUAAGACCAGCCUGGCCAACAUGGUGAAAUCCUGUCUCUACUAAAAAUAUAAAAUUAGCUGGGCAUGGUGGUGCACACCUGUCGUCUCAGCUACUCGGGAGGCAGAGGCAGGAGAAUGGCUUGAACCUGGGAAGCGGUUGCAGUGAGCCAAGAUUGCGCCUUUGCACUCCAGCCUGGGCAAGAGAGCAAGACUCUGUCUCAAAUAAUAAUAAUAAUAAUAAAGCUGGAGACUUGGCCACA